UGGCAAGUCCAGGACGAAGGGGCUGGGCCGGUUAGACGGCACGUGGGUGCCCAGUUAGGGGCUUAGGGCGUGAGAAAGAUAAUUAAGUUAAUGCAGGGGAAAAAUAUCUAGUUCUUCCUGGAAAGAAUUGGGGCGGUGAGAGGGGUUUUGGUGUGAAGACAUUAGGAAAUCGAUAUCCCCAAGGGAACGGUUUAGAGCUAAGGAGGGGUCCAGUUGUAAUGGAUGGGGUUAAAUUAAUGUGAAGAGGCCUUAAACCAAUGUGUCAGGAGGUUGGGUACCCUUGGAAUGCGUGGAAAGGAGUCUUUGUACAAAGAAGGAUUAAGUGUAUUUUAAAAGGGUGUCUGGGUGUCCCUAGAAUGAGCUGGGGAAGGUAGUCUUUUUUAAGUACAGGUAAUUAGGCCAAGGUGAAGAUGGGAUUUGGUUAUUGGAAGGGGAGGAAGUAGGGUGGGAGAGAUCUGUGUGCUAAAGUGAGGGGUGCCUGGGAAUUCCUGGAAUGAGACUGAGAGGUUGCUAAGACGCUGGGGGGUCUGAGUACCCCCAGAAUAGGAGGCUGGUGAGAGGGGCUUGAGUGUGAGGAAGAGGGGUCUGUGCUGGAUUAAGGUGGUGAUGGAGGUUCUGUAUGAGAAUAGGAGGUCCGGGUAUCCCUAAAGGGGGUUUGGGCAGCACGAGGGGUGUGUGUAAAAGGAGCUUAAGCCAUUGUGAAAGAUGGGUGUGUGGAUCUUUACACAAAGAAGAGGAGUUAUGUUGCUACGAAGAGGAGGGUCUGAGCAUCCCUAGAAUGGGUUAGGGUGGGUUGGGUCUUCUAGCAAAUUAAAAAAGAUUAGGUUAAUAAUGUGGAGGAGGAUCUGGAUAUUCCUGAGAUGGAUUUGAGGGGGGGCUCUGUUUGCAAGAGAGGCAUAGGUUGAUAUAAAAUGAGGGUAUGGGCAUCCCUGAAUGAGUGGCUGUGUAUGAACAGGAAGGGUUUAAAUCAAUGGGAAGAGGGGAUCUGGGUAUCUCAGAGGGGAUUAGAAUUGUCGAUUUGGUCUUGGUACAAAGAAGAGGUGAUGAAUGUAAAGAGUGGAUAGAUACCCUGGAGACAGGAGCUAGGGUGGUGGAAGGGCCUAGGUCCGAAGCGGGGAGGAGUAGGCUUUUGUGAAAAUGGGUCUGGGUAUUCUGGAUAGGGGGUUAGGGUUGUAGGAGAGGGCCUUGAUUUGUAGAGGAGGUUAAGUAAUUAAACAGGGCUGCGUAUCAUGAAGUGGUUAAGGUGGGCAAAGUCUGGGUGUGGAGAUGGGUUAGGCCAGUGUGAGAAAAUUUGACUGGGGGGAAGGGAUAUAGUUUGACGUGAGGAAUCUGGGCACCUGAGGAAGAGUUGGUGGGUAGCAGGGGUUGCGUGUAAAGGGGAGGGGUGGCACCUUGUACAGUGCUGAAAGUGGAGUGGUGGGGCAUUGGGCAGUUUGAGUGGUCUGAGUGUAAAAAGAAGUCUGAGAACCUGGGAGAAGGAGCAGAGGCCAUGGGAGGGGUGUGGCUGGGAGAAACAGGUGGGGAAGGCCUAUAUGGGGUUUCAGUUGGGUACCUUGGAGAGGAAUGGGGUGAGGUGAGUUGGUAAGAAAAGGAGUCAGUGGAAGGAGGUCUGAGUGGAGGUUCCCAUGUGCUGGGCGGAACUGUGGGGCCCACUGUGAGGUGUGGGAGAUGAGGGGACUGGACAGGUUACAAGGAUCUGGUGGGUGGAGUUUGAUGCAAGUUGAUACAGAGCCCAGGGCCUUGCUGCCGCCAUGACUGAGGAAUCAGAGGAGACAGUCCUGUACAUUGAGCACCGCUAUGUCUGCUCUGAGUGCAACCAGCUGUAUGGAUCACUGGAAGAGGUGCUUAUGCACCAAAACUCCCACGUGCCCCAGCAGCACUUUGAGCUGGUGGGCGUGGCUGAUCCCGGAGUCACUGUGGCCACAGACACAGCUUCAGGCACGGGCCUCUAUCAGACCCUUGUGCAGGAGAGCCAGUACCAGUGCCUGGAGUGUGGUCAACUGCUGAUGUCACCCAGCCAGCUCCUGGAGCACCAGGAGCUGCACCUGAAGAUGAUGGCACCCCAGGAGGCAGUGCCAGCUGAGCCAUCACCUAAGGCACCACCCCUGAGCUCCAGCACCAUCCACUACGAGUGUGUGGAUUGCAAGGCUCUCUUUGCCAGCCAGGAGCUCUGGCUGAACCACCGGCAGACGCACCUCCGGGCCACACCCACCAAGGCUCCUGCCCCUGUUGUCCUGGGGUCCCCAGUUGUUCUAGGGCCUCCUGUGGGCCAGGCCCGAGUGGCUGUGGAGCACUCAUACCGAAAGGCAGAAGAGGGUGGGGAAGGGGCGACUGUCCCAUCUGCCGCUGCCACCACCACUGAGGUAGUGACUGAGGUGGAGCUGCUCCUCUACAAGUGCUCUGAGUGCUCCCAGCUCUUCCAGCUGCCGGCGGAUUUCCUGGAGCACCAGGCCACUCACUUCCCUGCUCCUGUACCCGAGUCUCAGGAGCCUGCCUUACAGCAGGAGGUGCAGGCCUCGUCACCUGCAGAGGUGCCUGUGUCUCAGCCUGACCCCUUGCCAGCUUCUGACCACAGUUACGAGCUGCGCAAUGGUGAAGCCAUUGGGCGGGAUCGCCGGGGGCGCAGGGCCCGGAGGAACAACAGUGGAGAAGCAGGCGGGGCAGCCACACAGGAGCUCUUCUGCUCAGCCUGUGACCAGCUCUUUCUCUCACCCCACCAGCUACAGCAGCACCUGCGGAGUCACCGGGAGGGCGUCUUUAAGUGCCCCCUGUGCAGUCGUGUCUUCCCUAGCCCUUCCAGUCUGGACCAGCACCUUGGAGACCAUAGCAGCGAGUCACACUUCCUGUGUGUAGACUGUGGCCUGGCCUUCGGCACAGAGGCCCUCCUCCUGGCCCACCGGCGAGCCCACACCCCGAAUCCUCUGCAUUCAUGUCCAUGUGGGAAGACCUUUGUCAACCUUACCAAGUUCCUUUAUCACCGGCGUACUCAUGGGGUAGGGGGUGUCCCUCUGCCCACAACACCAGUCCCACCAGAGGAACCUGUCAUUGGUUUCCCUGAGCCAGCCCCAGCAGAGACUGGAGAGCCAGAGGCCCCUGAGCCCCCUGUGUCUGAGGAGACCUCAGCAGGGCCCGCUGCCCCAGGCACCUACCGCUGCCUCCUGUGCAGCCGUGAAUUUGGAAAGGCCUUGCAGCUGACCCGGCACCAACGUUUUGUGCAUCGGCUGGAGCGGCGCCAUAAAUGCAGCAUUUGUGGCAAGAUGUUCAAGAAGAAGUCUCACGUGCGUAACCACCUGCGCACACACACAGGGGAGCGGCCCUUCCCCUGCCCUGACUGCUCCAAGCCCUUCAACUCACCUGCCAACCUGGCCCGCCACCGGCUCACACACACAGGAGAGCGGCCCUACCGGUGUGGGGACUGUGGCAAGGCUUUCACGCAAAGCUCCACACUGAGGCAGCACCGCUUGGUGCAUGCCCAGCACUUCCCCUACCGCUGCCAGGAAUGUGGGGUGCGUUUUCACCGUCCUUACCGCCUGCUCAUGCACCGCUACCAUCACACAGGUGAAUACCCCUACAAGUGUCGCGAGUGCCCCCGCUCCUUCUUGCUGCGUCGGCUGCUGGAGGUGCACCAGCUCGUGGUCCAUGCCGGGCGCCAGCCCCACCGCUGCCCAUCCUGUGGGGCUGCCUUCCCCUCCUCACUGCGGCUCCGGGAGCACCGCUGUGCAGCCGCUGCUGCCCAGGCCCCACGGCGCUUUGAGUGUGGCACCUGUGGCAAGAAAGUGGGCUCAGCUGCUCGACUGCAGGCACACGAGGCGGCCCAUGCAGCUGCUGGGCCUGGAGAGGUCCUGGCUAAGGAGCCCCCUGCCCCUCGAGCCCCACGGGCCACUCGUGCACCAGUUGCCUCUCCAGCAGCCCUUGGAAGCACUGCUACAGCAUCCCCUGCGGCCCCUGCCCGCCGCCGGGGUCUAGAGUGCAGCGAGUGCAAGAAGCUGUUCAGCACAGAGACGUCACUGCAGGUGCACCGGCGCAUCCACACAGGUGAGCGGCCAUACCCAUGUCCAGACUGUGGCAAAGCGUUCCGUCAGAGUACCCACCUGAAAGACCACCGGCGCCUGCACACAGGUGAGCGGCCCUUUGCCUGUGAAGUGUGUGGCAAGGCCUUUGCCAUCUCCAUGCGCCUGGCAGAACAUCGCCGCAUCCACACAGGCGAACGACCCUACUCCUGCCCUGACUGUGGCAAGAGCUACCGCUCCUUCUCCAACCUCUGGAAGCACCGCAAGACCCAUCAGCAGCAGCAUCAGGCAGCUGUGCGGCAGCAGCUGGCAGAGGCGGAGGCUGCCGUUGGCCUGGCCGUCAUGGAGACUGCUGUGGAGGCGCUACCCCUGGUGGAAGCCAUUGAGAUCUACCCUCUGGCCGAGGCUGAGGGGGUCCAGAUCAGUGGCUGACUCUGCCCGACUUCCUCUUUGGCACCUCCAUUCCCUGUUGCUGAAGGCCCUCCAGCAUCCCCUUAAGCAUCUGUACAUACUGUGUCCCUUCCUCUUCCCAUCCCCACCACCUUGUAAGUUCUAAAUUGGAUUUAUUCUCUCGUGAGGGGGGUGCUCUGGGGUCCUUGACACACAUAAAGGUGCCCCCCCACCUUCCACCUCUUAGCACUGGUGACCCCAAAAAUGAAACCAUCAAUAAAGACUGAGUUGCCAGCA